CUGUCCUUUCCCGGGAGUUAGCGAUCCCUCAACCCCUGCACUGCGCUAGUCCUAAAGAGGAAAUGUCUCUACGCUGCGGGGAUGCAGCCCGCACCCUGGGGCCCCGGGUAUUUGGGAGAUAUUUUUGCAGCCCAGUCAGACCGUUAAGCUCCUUGCCAGAUAAAAAAAAGGAACUCCUACAGAAUGGACCAGACCUUCAAGAUUUUGUAUCUGGUGAUCUUGCAGACAGGAGCACCUGGGAUGAAUAUAAAGGAAACCUAAAACGCCAGAAAGGAGAAAGGUUAAGACUACCUCCAUGGCUAAAGACAGAGAUUCCCAUGGGGAAAAAUUACAAUAAACUGAAAAAUACUUUGCGGAAUUUAAAUCUCCAUACAGUAUGUGAGGAAGCUCGAUGUCCCAAUAUUGGAGAGUGUUGGGGAGGUGGAGAAUAUGCCACCGCCACAGCCACGAUCAUGUUGAUGGGUGACACAUGUACAAGAGGUUGCAGAUUUUGUUCUGUUAAGACUGCAAGAAAUCCUCCUCCACUGGAUGCCAGUGAGCCCUACAAUACUGCAAAGGCAAUUGCAGAAUGGGGUCUGGAUUAUGUUGUCCUGACAUCUGUGGAUCGAGAUGAUAUGCCUGAUGGGGGAGCUGAACACAUUGCAAAGACCGUAUCAUAUUUAAAGGAAAGGAAUCCAAAAAUCCUUGUGGAGUGUCUUACUCCUGAUUUUCGAGGUGAUCUCAAAGCAAUAGAAAAAGUUGCUCUGUCAGGAUUAGAUGUGUAUGCACAUAAUGUAGAAACAGUCCCGGAAUUACAGAGUAAGGUUCGUGAUCCUCGGGCCAAUUUUGAUCAGUCCCUACGUGUACUGAAACAUGCCAAGAAGGUUCAGCCUGAUGUUAUUUCUAAAACAUCUAUAAUGUUGGGUUUAGGCGAGAAUGAUGAGCAAGUAUAUGCAACAAUGAAAGCACUUCGUGAGGCAGAUGUAGACUGCUUGACUUUAGGACAAUAUAUGCAGCCAACAAGGCGUCACCUUAAGGUUGAAGAAUAUAUUACUCCUGAAAAAUUCAAAUACUGGGAAAAAGUAGGAAAUGAACUUGGAUUUCAUUAUACUGCAAGUGGCCCUUUGGUGCGUUCUUCAUAUAAAGCAGGUGAAUUUUUCCUGAAAAAUCUAGUGGCUAAAAGAAAAACAAAAGACCUCUAAAACUUCAACAAGACCUUCAAGAUCACAGAAAUUUUUAAAAUUUGAUUCCAGUUAAUAACAGAGGUGGUGCCAGAAUGCCUGGACUGCAGUGGAUGUGCCCCACCUCUUUGCUUAAAAAAAAAAAUGUCAAUAGCCAGGCAUAGUGGCUCACGCCUGUAAUCCCAGCACUUUAGGAGGCCAAGGCGGGUGGAUCACCUGAGGUCAGGAGUUCGAGACCAGCCUGGCCAACAUGGUGAAAUCCUGUCUCCACUAAAAACACAAAAAUUAGUCAGGCGUGGUAGUGGGUGCCUGUAAUCCCAGCUACUCGGGAGGCUAAGGCAGGAGAAUCACUUGAACCUGGGAGGGGGAGGUUGCAGUGAGCCAAGAUCGCUCCAUUGCCCUCCAGCCUGGGUGACAAGAGCAAAACUCCAUCUCAAAUAAAUAAAAAGGAAAAAAAAGUCAAUAAACUGUACAAAUUUAAUUACAGUAAUUCAUUUGGCUUUUAGUGUAUCUUCUUUGUCCCAAUUAAACAGUUGCUUGCUGUGAUGUAAUCUUAAAAUAUCUUUGUAAGAAUUUUCUUUUAACAUAAUUUUAAAAUGCAUUAAAAACAUGGCAUGGUGGCUCACACCUAUAAUCCCAACAUUUUGGGAGGCCAGGGCGGGUGGAUCACUUGAACCCAGGAGUUCGAGACCAGCCUGGGCAACAUGAUGAGACCUUAUCUCUACAAAAAAUUAGCCAGACGUGGUGGCACGCACCCGUAGUCCCAGCUACUCAGGCUGAGGUGAGAGGAUCACUUGAACCUGGAAAGCAGAGGUUGCAAUGAGCUGAGGUGGUGCCACUGCUCUCCAGCCUGGGCGCUACAACUGCUCUCCAGACUCUGUCUUGAAAAAAAAACCCAAAAACUUCCAGAAGAUUUUCCAAUCCACUGUUAACAUCAUUACAUUUCAUUUAUGAAAAAUAAAAACUUCAUUUAUGUUACUGUGAUGAAACAGUCAACAUAGAUUGAAACUCAUCAGUUUAGCAUUUCAUUCAACUUUAGCAUUCAUUCAACGUAGAUUGAAACUCAUCAGAUUAGCAUUUGUCCUUGUAAUAUUGGAAUAAUUUAGAAAGGCUUAAGAGUGAAUGUUGGCCAGAUGUGGUGGCUCAUGCCUGUAAUUCCAGCACUCUGAGAGGCCGAGGUGGGCAGAUCACCUGAGGUCGGGAGUUUGAGAACAGCCUGGCCAACCUGGUGAAACUCCAUUGCUACUAAAAAUAAAAAAAUUAGCUAGGUGUGUUGGCAGGUGCCUGUAAUCCCAGCUACUUGGGAGGCUGAGGCACGAGAAUUACUUGAGCCUGUGAAGCAGAGAUUGCAGUGAGGCGAUAUCGUGCCACUGCACUCCAGCCCGGGCAACAGAGUGAGACUGUCUCAAAAAAAAAGUAAAUGUUGAUUUUUUACAUUGGUGUGACUACUUCAGAACCUGCAAAAUAGUUUUAUGCUGAUUACAUUUAGUCCCUCUGAAAACACCAAGGCCAUAAUGCUGCCUAAGACAUGGAAAUAGAACCUAGAAAUAUUAACCCUUAUUUGUAUAGUAGCUUGCUAAAUCCACAUGCCCUAUUCCUUUCAUUUCUCACAUUGGUUGUAUUAUAUGAUGGUAAAGGCCUGAGAAAGGAAUUUCCUUCCAAAAUACUAAUAACUCAGAUUCAUCUUUUGACUGAAUCCUGCCUUUCUACUUUUUCUGCAUAUCUAAAAGGACACUUUUAGGUGGCCAUGUUGUAAAAUAUGUAAAGUGGAUAGCCAAUUCUGUUUUGAAUUCUUAUAACGAGCCAGUAUUAUAAAAGUAAUGCACAUCCUUGCCAGGUGUGGUGGCUCACGCCUGUAAUCCCACCACCUUGGGAGGCUGAGGCGGGUGAAUCAGUUGAGCUCAGGAGUUUGAGACUAGCCUGGGCAACACAGUCAGACCCCCAUCUCUACCAAAAAUACAAAAAAUUAGCUGGGUGUGGUGGCACAUGCUUGUAAUCUCAGCUAUUUGGGAGGCUGAGGCAGGAGAAUCACUUGAACCUGACAGGCAGAGGUUGCAGUGAGCUGAGAUCACAUCACUGUACUCCAGCCUGGGUGACAGAGACCGUGUCUCAAAAAAAAUUUUUUUAAGUAAUGCAUGGGCCGGGCAUGGUGGCUUAAUGCCUGUAAUUCCAACGUUUUGGGAGGCCGAGGCAGGUGGAUCACCUGAGGUCAGGAGUUUGAGACCAGCCUGAACAACAUGGUGAAACACUGUCUCUACUAAAAAUUAAAAAAUUAGCCAAGUGUGGUGGCGCAUGUCUGUAAUCCCAGCUACUCAGGAGGCUGAGACAGGAGAAUCCUUGAACCUGGGAGGCAGAGGUUGCAGUGAGCUGAGAUCACACCAUUGCACUCCAGCCUGGACAACGAGUGAAACU